AUAAGCUCCAGCCUUCCUGUGGCCACAGCAGGACCAGAGUGGACCAGCACACCCCAGGAGAGAGGACUGGGGUCCCAGGAGUAGGAGGAGCCCGAGCACCAUGAGCUCCGGAGACCCUGCACACCUCGGCCUCUGCCUCUGGCUGUGGCUGGGCGCCACCCUGGGAAGAGAGCAAGUUCAAGCAAGCGGUCUCCUGAGGCUGGCUGUGCUGCCUGAGGACCGGCUGCAGAUGAAGUGGAGAGAGUCGGAGGGGAGCGGCCUCGGCUACCUGGUGCAGGUGAAGCCCAUGGCAGGGGACUCGGAACAGGAGGUGAUACUGACCACCAAGACCCCUAAGGCCACAGUGGGGGGCCUGAGCCCCUCCAAGGGCUACACCUUGCAGAUCUUCGAGCUCACUGGCUCUGGGCGCUUCCUGCUAGCUCGGAGGGAGUUUGUGAUUGAGGAUCUGAAGAGUAGCUCCCUGGACAGGAGCAGCCAGAGGCCCCUCGGCUCUGGAGCCCCGGAGCCCACCCCCUCCCACACGGGGAGCCCAGACCCUGAGCAGGCUUCUGAGCCCCAAGUUGCCUUCACACCAAGCCAGGAUCCGCGCACUCCUGCCGGCCCCCAGUUCCGCUGCCUGCCCCCCGUGCCUGCUGACAUGGUCUUCCUGGUGGACGGGUCCUGGAGCAUUGGCCACAGUCACUUCCAGCAGGUCAAGGACUUCCUGGCCAGUGUCAUCGCACCCUUUGAAAUCGGGCCGGAUAAGGUCCAAGUAGGCCUGACUCAGUACAGCGGGGAUGCUCAGACUGAGUGGGACCUGAACUCCCUCAGCACCAAGGAACAGGUGCUGGCAGCUGUGCGCCGCCUCCGCUACAAGGGGGGGAACACGUUCACAGGCCUUGCCCUGACCCACGUGCUGGGGCAGAACCUGCAGCCGGCGGCUGGCCUCCGUCCAGAGGCAGCCAAGGUGGUGAUUCUGGUGACGGACGGCAAGUCCCAGGACGAUGUGCACACUGCUGCCCGUGUCCUCAAGGACCUGGGCGUGAACGUCUUCGCUGUGGGUGUGAAGAACGCCGAUGAGGCUGAGCUGAGGCUCCUGGCGUCCCCGCCGAGGGACAUCACCGUCCACAGCGUGCUGGACUUCCUGCAGCUCGGCGCGCUGGCUGGCCUGCUCAGCCGUCUCAUCUGCCAGAGGCUCCAGGGUGGGAGCCCGCGGCAGGGCCCAGCAGCAGCGGCUCCAGCCCUGGACACCCUCCCUGCCCCCACCAGCCUGGUCCUGAGCCAGGUGACCUCCUCCAGCAUCCGCCUGUCCUGGACUCCAGCCCCCCGGCACCCCCUCAAGUAUCUGAUCGUUUGGCGAGCCUCUAGAGGUGGCACCCCCAGGGAGGUGGUGGUGGAGGGACCCGCCGCCUCCACGGAGCUGCACAACCUGGCCUCCCGCACAGAGUACCUGGUCUCCGUGUUCCCCAUCUAUGAGGGCGGGGUUGGCGAAGGCCUGCGGGGCCUGGUGACCACAGCACCUCUGCCUCCGCCCCGGGCGCUGACCCUGGCCGCAGUGACGCCCAGAACCGUCCACCUCACCUGGCAGCCCUCGGCCGGGGCCACCCACUACCUGGUGCGAUGUUCUCCUGCUUCCCCCAAGGGUGAAGAGGAGGAGCGAGAGGUGCAGGUCGGGCGGCCCGAGGUGCUGCUGGAUGGCCUGGAACCUGGCAGGGACUAUGAGGUCUCGGUGCAGAGCCUGCGAGGCCCUGAGGGCAGCGAGGCCCGGGGCAUCCGUGCCAGGACCCCCACCCUGGCCCCCCCGAGACACCUGGGCUUCUCAGACGUGAGCCACGACGCGGCACGAGUGUUCUGGGAGGGUGCCCCGAGGCCUGUGCGCCUGGUCAGGGUCACCUAUGUGUCCAGCGAGGGUGGACACUCGGGGCAGACAGAGGCUCCUGGGAACGCCACCUCGGCCACGCUGGGGCCUCUCUCUUCCUCCACCACCUACACUGUCCGUGUCACCUGCCUCUACCCUGGGGGUGGCUCCUCUACGCUGACUGGCCGGGUGACCACCAAGAAAGCUCCCAGCCCAAGCCAGCUGUCCAUGACGGAGCUGCCAGGGGAUGCAGUCCAGCUGGCGUGGGUGGCCGCAGCCCCGUCUGGCGUGCUUGUCUACCAGAUCACGUGGACGCCCCUGGGAGAGGGGAAGGCUCACGAGAUCUCUGUCCCAGGGAACCUCGGCACGGCCGUCCUGCCUGGCCUAGGGAGGCACACAGAGUACGACGUCACCAUCUUGGCCUACUACAGGGACGGGGCCCGCAGUGACCCUGUGUCCCUCCGCUAUACCCCCUCCACGGUGAGCAGGAGCCCACCCUCCAACCUGGCCCUGGCCUCGGAGACCCCCGACAGCCUGCAGGUCAGCUGGACGCCCCCGCUUGGCCGCGUGCUCCAUUACUGGCUCACCUACGCCCCCGCCUCUGGCUUGGGACCCGAGAAAUCCGUCUCUGUGCCAGGAGCCAGGAGCCACGUGACACUGCCCGACCUGCAGGCAGCCACGAAGUACAGGGUCCUGGUCUCAGCUAUCUAUGCAGCAGGCAGGAGUGAGGCUGUGUCUGCCACGGGCCAGACAGCAGCCUGCCCAGCCCUCCGCCCUGACGGCUCCCUCCCAGGGUUUGACCUGAUGGUGGCCUUCAGCCUGGUGGAAAAGGCUUAUGCGUCCAUCCGGGGCGUGGCCAUGGAGCCCUCUGCCUUCGGUGGGACCCCGACCUUCACGCUCUUCAAGGACGCCCAGCUGACAAGACGGGUCAGUGACGUCUACCCAGCCCCCCUACCUCCAGAGCACACCAUCGUCUUCCUUGUGCGCCUACUUCCCGAGACACCCCGUGAGGCCUUCGCGCUGUGGCAGAUGACAGCCGAGGACUUCCAGCCCCUCCUUGGGGUUCUGCUGGAUGCCGGGAAGAAGUCCCUGACCUACUUCCACCGUGACCCCAGGGCUGCCUUGCAGGAGGCCACCUUCGACCCGCAGGAAGUGAGGAAGAUUUUCUUCGGGAGCUUCCACAAGGUGCACGUGGCUGUGGGCCGCUCCAAGGUCAGGCUCUAUGUGGACUGCCGGAAGGUGGCUGAGCGGCCCCUUGGGGAGAUGGGCAGCCCACCCGCUGCGGGCUUCGUCACGCUGGGGAGGCUGGCCAAGGCCAGGGGCCCCCGGAGCAGUUCGGCCGCGUUUCAGCUCCAGAUGCUGCAGAUCGUGUGCAGUGACACCUGGGCCGAUGAGGACCGGUGCUGUGAGCUCCCUGCCUCGAGGGAUGGAGAGACCUGCCCCGCCUUCGUGUCUGCCUGUUCCUGUUCCUCAGAGACCCCUGGGCCCCCAGGACCUCAAGGACCCCCAGGCCUCCCUGGGAGGAAUGGCACCCCAGGAGAGCAGGGCUUCCCAGGGCCCAGGGGAGAGCCCGGGCCACCCGGACAGAUGGGACCAGAAGGUCCUGGAGGCCAGCAGGGCUCGCCGGGGACCCAGGGCCGUGCAGUCCAGGGGCCUGUGGGUCCACCAGGGGUCAAAGGAGAGAAGGGAGACCAUGGGCUUCCAGGCUUGCAGGGCCACCCCGGCCACCAGGGCAUCCCCGGGAGAGUUGGCCUCCAGGGACCAAAGGGAAUGAGAGGCCUGGAGGGAACUGCUGGCCUGCCUGGACCCCCUGGCCCCAGGGGGUUCCAGGGCAUGGCAGGGGCCAGGGGCACUAGUGGAGAGCGAGGACCUCCAGGGACCGUGGGGCCCACAGGACUGCCAGGGCCCAAAGGGGAACGAGGAGAGAAGCACACGUGUCAAAGUUCGACUCCUUCCACGAGAACACCAGGCCCCCCAUGCCCAUCUUGGAGCAGAAGCUGGAGCCGGGCACUGAGCCCCUGGGGUCCCCUGGCACCCGCAGCAAGGCCCUGGUUCCUGGAGAAUGGGGGCGUGGUGGCCGCCACCUUGAGGGCAGAGGGGAGCCUGGAGCUGUUGGUCAGAUGGGCAGCCCUGGGCAGCAGGGGGCUAGCACCCAGGGCCUCUGGGAGUGACAGGACAUUUUCUGCACUGCCCCGAGGAACGCUGAGCCUUCCUCCCUGGGUUUGUCUGGACACCGAGAGCGACCACAUCCUGGAGAAGCCAGGAGAAAAGCUCAGGAAGAGCCUGCAGGUGGAAGGAGAGGGAAGCAGCGGCCUCGGCCAAGGCCCACCCCAUACUCUUGGCUCUGUAGCAUUUCCAAGUUCAGAUAAACCCCUGAGUGCUCACCCAGCCAAGCGAGGCGGGAGUCAUUUCCUGGGAGAGUGUCCCCCACCCUGGCUCUGUGCACCCCACCUUGAGGCCCUGCAGCUUCAGCCGCAGUGGGGAAGGGGAGGGGCUGGGCUGAUGGCGAAUCGGGUUCAGGAGGGCAGCAGUGCCCUGUGGCCGUCUCAGUAGCUCUAAAACAGGCUCAACAACAUGCCCCGCCCCUUUCUCUGGGCCUCAUCUAAGCCUGGCCAGGGCCCUGUGGGCCCGCCUCUCUCUGCGCCUCACGCAGGCAACAGAUGGUUCCACUGCUGGCCCACCAGUCACCUGCACGAUGGCUCCUCCCUCAGAACAGCACUCCCACCCCGGCCCCAGCACCUUCACAUCUGGGCACAGGCAGGUCCCUGCCUGCCUCAUCGUCCCCUCUGUCCCCAGCCCAAGAAGGAGUUCAGAUCCUGUGUGUGAAUGGCCACCCCUCACCCACCCAGCCCUGUGCUGAGUUCCUUGUGCAGGGACAUUGCUUUGAGACUUGGCACCAUCAGCCCCUGGUCCUUAGGGUCUCAGAGCAAGGUCAUCCCUCAGCAGGCUUCUGGCCUGUGCGCUCCUCAGCACCUCUGCCCAGGUCUCUCCCAACCAUCACAGACGCUGUGUGAGCCUGGACUUCCUGCCUUAUCCCCACUGUGGCCCAAACAGCAUGGGGGCAAGCUCAGAACACACACCUGGGCUUCUGGGCCUUGUGGCCCGUGGGGGUGAUGUGGGAACUUCUACUUCCUUUCCAAACAAAUAUUCAGUAACUAGUCCACUGUUACCACUUAGGCAGCUAAGCAAGAAAGGUGCCAGAAAUGAAGAGGGAAGCCAUAUCAUUGAGGAGAGAAUGAAAAGUAUUAAAAAGGAACAAAGAGAGACCCUUGAUAUUGACAGAAGGAAAACCCACCAAGAUCACCAGUGCAGCAUUGCGUGCACCAAAGCAUACCCCAAAGAGGUGAGCGCAAAACAGCUUCAGGGCAAACACUUCAUCUAUGAUUCAACUGUUCCAGGAACUGACCAGACCUGGAGACCAAAUAGAGAGUCAUAGGCAGGGUCAGCAGGAUGGGAGAGAGCGCCUGCACCCACAGGAGCCACAGCCCUGACUGAGGCCAGGAAGCAGCCCCAAAUGCCAGCUCCCACUGCAGCAUGAGAACAGAAACAGACCACUGAAAAUUCCCAAAGUCUGUGGACAAAUCAGACGUCGAAGAAGUCACGUGGCAUCGAGACAGAUUUUGCACUGAGGGACAAGGAGAGCAUGUGGCCAAAGUAGGUGCAGGUAAAGCAGCAUCUGGGGCAGAGUUAUAGCCUUCAGUGCAGGUAUCAGACACAGUUGUUGAGAGCAGCAGCCCAAGCCAGCCCCUCCGUCCUGCAGGGAGGACACCUAGGUCACUUGGCUUCUGUUGGGGAGCUGAGUUGCUUCAGAUUGUGUGACCAGCAAAACAGCUUGGUUGCUCUCACUUGGUUUCUCCAGGGCGGGGAAUUACAUGUCCCCAGCUGAACUGAGAAGGCUCUUUGAGCAGUGGAGUGAGCAGGCUUUGUCAUGAGGCAGGAGUGGGGCUAGAAUCAAGCCCAGAGCCCACAGGGCAUCCAGAGCCUUCCAAAGGAGCCCCUCUCCUGGGGCUCUCCAAUUUGAUGAAGGGACUGGGCACUGGGUGGCUGAGACCACAUUGGCAGCCAGGAGGAGGCAGCCUGGCCGGGGGGAACCAGGGUGGCUCUAAUCCCCACCACCCCCUCAGCUGCCCUACCCCCGCCACGCUGGUGUGACACCAGUGAUGCUCAGCCUCAAAAGGGGAGUCCGGCUGUCUUCGGGAAACUGACUUUAUGCUGGAGGCCAAUUAAAAUGGCACAGCAAAGGCAGCGGCCAGCUGGUGCCCAGGCAGCUUAGGGACUGGUCCCUGAGGCCCCACCCGCCCCAGCCUGUGCAGUGGAGCUGAGUACGAAUCAAAGGUGAGGAUGGCAAGGGAGCUGAGAGCAGCCUCCGGAUGCACCAAACCGGCCUGGCUCCUGUUUGCAGGAAGGCAGCCUCCCCGAGACCCAGCCGACCUGCACGUCUCCCAUCAGCCCCGACUCCACCGCAUCCCUCUGGGUCCUUUUAGGAGCCCCCAGGGACUGAGCCGGGGCUCACGCUCCUGGCCAGAGCGCUGGGUUUCUGGCAAUGCCUCCCCUCCUGCCUUUACGGCCACAGCUCUCCCCUCCAGAGGCCCCUCUGUAGUGGGCCUCGGUCCCCUCUCCACCCCCAGAGGCAGCACAGCUUCAGCCCUACGCAGUGUGGGGGCUCCGGGAGGAAAUGCAGGGAGGUGCUUGGUCUUGGCCCAGAGCUCAUGGCCUUAGGUGCUGCCCCCAGUCACCCCCGUGCCCAUGCAGCCGGGGAUGUUCAGCUCAGGCCAGCCACCGAGGUGGUGUGACGCAAGGCUGAUCUGACGCUCAGCUCAGGCCGCUGGGGUCAUGGGGGUUGUGGGAAGGUCAUGGAAUCACGGGGCUCACGCUGGGGUCACAGGGUGGUGUGGCUGUGUGGACUGUAAGGGGCGUGCAGCCAUGCGUAUCUGACCUGCCCUCCCUAGGUCUGCAGGCAGUGCCGAGUGGCUCUGCCUGAGGCCCCAAGAGCGACCUUGGAAGCUCCAGGCCUUCACAGCCCCUCUGAGAGCCACCUGCAAGGUGGGGAGCUGGGAAGAACGGCUCAGUGAUGAGCUCAGAGGGAGGGGUGGGCACAGCGCCCAGGAAGGCGGGUGCGUGCAGGCCUGGGAGGAAUGUGUAGCAGGAGGCAGGGGGUGCUGUGCCCGCAGGACCAGCAGGUGAGGCGUGUCCACCCACAGAGGAUGGCUCUGGCCCAGGCAGUGUCAGAAAUGGAAGCUGAGGAAACCCAACCCCAGCUGUAGAGGAGCCUGCCCCGAUGCCAUCUGCACCUGGGGGGCGACGUAUGGCUGCCAGCCUCUUCAUCUACCAAGGACCAGGGCAGUGGGGACGGGAGAGCUGGGACACGUGGACUCACACCAGGGCAGAUGGUGGGGGAAGCCAGUGUCUGUAGAUUCAGUGCAUUUCUUGGGGAAGGGCGUGGAACAUUUGGACUUGAGCCCCAGCACAGAGACGAUGUCAUAAUACAGCCCCCCAUCGUGAUCUGAUGGUAAGUACAGAACUCCUUGCCCAGUGGAGAAACACUCUCCUCUCAUGUGUGGAAUAUCCACACACUAACCAUGAACUGGGCCAUAAGAAACCUUACAUUCCAAAGGAUCCUGCUGUUCAGAACUCACUCACUCACUGAUGAAACUGGAAAAACAACCAAUGAUAACAAGCUAAAGAAUGCCUCUAGAAGCUAAAAGACACACCCAUGACUCCACAGUAAUUCAUGGGUUAAAGAGAAAAAAGGAAACGUGAAGAUACUUGUAACCAAAUAAUGAUGGAUGCAGCGCCACGUCAGAAUCUCUGUGCUGCAGCUGCAGUGGUACCUAGAGGGCAAUUUAUAGCUGUAAAUACAGUGCUUUGUUUUGUUUUCUUGUUUUUUGAGACAAGGUCUUGCUCUGUCACCCAGGCUGGAGUACAGUGGCAUGAUCUCGGCUCAAUGCAACCUCUGUGCCACCCUGGGCUCAAGUGGUCCUCCUGCUCCGGUCUUCUGAGUAGCAGGAACCACAGGCGUGCGCCACCACGCUUGGCUAAUGUUUUUUGUAUUUUUUUAAAUAGAGACAGGGUGUUGCCGUGUUACCCAGGCUGGUCUUGAACUUCUGAGCUCAAACGAUCCACCCUCCUUGGCCUCCCAAAGUGGUGGGAUUACAGGUGUGAGUCACCUCACCGGCCCUUAAACACAGUUUUUAGGGAAGAUUCCAACUCAAACAAUUUUAAAUAGUAGAAAAUAAACCCUGAAGCAGUGUGCAUUCAUUA